AGGUGAGGGAGACUGGGUCCUGGCCUUUGGGCAUCAUCCAGCGCCAUCGGCCUGGCGCUUCAGCCAACGCGGGAGUGGAUGGGCCCCUUCUUCUUCGCAGACAGCGUUCGGCCGCUGCCCGGGCUCUAGGCGCGGCCGGACGGCCCAGUCUGGAGGGUUCGGGGCGGAGGCCCGGGGGGGUGCGCGCGCCCGGGGUCCGGCCUCUCACUCGCUCCCCUCUCGUCCGCAGCCGCAGGGCCGUAGGCAGCCAUGGCGCCCAGCCGGAAUGGCAUGGUCUUGAAGCCCCACUUCCACAAGGACUGGCAGCGGCGCGUGGCCACGUGGUUCAACCAGCCGGCCCGUAAGAUCCGCAGACGUAAGGCCCGGCAAGCCAAGGCGCGCCGCAUCGCCCCGCGCCCCGCGUCGGGUCCCAUCCGGCCCAUCGUGCGCUGCCCCACGGUUCGGUACCACACGAAGGUGCGCGCCGGCCGCGGCUUCAGCCUGGAGGAGCUCAGGGUGGCCGGCAUUCACAAGAAGGUGGCCCGGACCAUCGGCAUUUCUGUGGAUCCGAGGAGGCGGAACAAGUCCACGGAGUCCCUGCAGGCCAACGUGCAGCGGCUGAAGGAGUACCGCUCCAAACUCAUCCUCUUCCCCAGGAAGCCCUCGGCCCCCAAGAAGGGAGACAGUUCUGCUGAAGAACUGAAACUGGCCACCCAGCUGACCGGACCGGUCAUGCCCGUCCGGAACGUCUAUAAGAAGGAGAAAGCUCGAGUCAUCACUGAGGAAGAGAAGAAUUUCAAAGCCUUCGCUAGUCUCCGUAUGGCCCGUGCCAACGCCCGGCUCUUCGGCAUACGGGCAAAAAGAGCCAAGGAAGCCGCAGAACAGGAUGUUGAAAAGAAAAAAUAAAGCCCUCCUGGGGACUUGGAAUCAGUCGGCAGUCAUGCUGGGUCUCCACGUGGUGUGUUUCGUGGGAACAACUGGGCCUGGGAUGGGGCUUCACUGCUGUGACUUCCUCCUGCCAGGGGAUUUGGGGCUUUCUUGAAAGACAGUCCAAGCCCUGGAUAAUGCUUUACUUUCUGUGUUGAAGCACUGUUGGUUGUUUGGUUAGUGACUGAUGUAAAACGGUUUUCUUGUGGGGAGGUUACAGAGGCUGACUUCAGAGUGGACUUGUGUUUUUUCUUUUUAAAGAGGCAAGGUUGGGCUGGUGCUCACAGCUGUAAUCCCAGCACUUUGAGGUUGGCUGGGAGUUCAAGACCAGCCUGGCCAACAUGUCAGAACUACUAAAAAUAAAGAAAUCAGCCAUGCUUGGUGCUGCACACUUGUAGUUGCAGCUCCUGGGAGGCAGAGGUGAGGGAUCACUUAACCCAGGAGGCAGAGGCUGCACUGAGCCAGGAUCACGCCACUGCACUCUAGCCUGGGCAACAGUGAGACUGUCUCAAAAAAAAAAAAAGAGACAGGGUCUUCGGCACCCAGGCUGGAGUACAGUGCCACAAUCAUGGCUCACUGCAGUCUUGAACUCAUGGCCUCAAGCAGUCCUCCCUCAGCCUCCCAAGUAGAGGGGUUUAUAGGCACGAGACCCUGCACCCAACCUAGAGUUGCCUUUUUUAAGCAAAGCAGUUUCUAGUUAAUGUAGCAUCUUGGACUUUGGGGCGUCAUUCUUAAGCUUGUUGUGCCCGGUAACCAUGGUCCUCUUGCUCUGAUUAACCCUUCCUUCAAUGGGCUUCUUCACCCAGACACCAAGGUAUGAGAUGGCCCUGCCAAGUGUCGGCCUCUCCUGUUAAACAAAAACAUUCUAAAGCCAUUGUUCUUGCUUCAUGGACAAGAGGCAGCCAGAGAGAGUGCCAGGGUGCCCUGGUCUGAGCUGGCAUCCCCAUGUCUUCUGUGUCCGAGGGCAGCAUGGUUUCUCGUGCAGUGCUCAGACACAGCCUGCCCUAGUCCUACCAGCUCACAGCAGCACCUGCUCUCCUUGGCAGCUAUGGCCAUGACAACCCCAGAGAAGCAGCUUCAGGGACCGAGUCAGAUUCUGUUUUGUCUACAUGCCUCUGCCGGGUGCCGGUAUUGAGGCACCCAGGGAGCUGUUACUGGCGUGGAAAUAGGUGAUGCUGCUACCUCUGCUGCUGCACUCACAGCCACACUUGAUACACGAUGACACCUUGCUUGUUUGGAAACAUCUAAACAUCUAGUAGAUGACUUGCAGGCUGUUGGCUACCAGUUUCCUGUCUGAGGUGUAUAUGUUAACUUCGUGAUCAGUUUGUAUGUUUGGGACUCUUGUCCUAUGUAAAGUUAAGGUGGGCCGGGUGCAGUGGCUCACGCCUGUAAUCCUAACACUGGGAGGCCGAGGCGGGUGGAUCACCUGAUGGUGAAACCUCAUCUCUACUGAAAAUACAAAAAUUAGCUGAGUGGUGACACACGCCUGUAAUCCCAGCUACUUGGUAGGCUUGAACCCAGGAGGCAGAGAUUGCAGUGAGCCGAGCUGCACCACUGUGCUCCAGCCUGGGUGACAGCGAGACUCAGUCUCAAAAAAAGUUGUACAAGGUGGAUGGUUGGAAGCUUGAGCCUAGGCUCGAAUCCCUCUCACGUGAGAGGGCCUGAAGAUUUCUGGUGGAUUCCAACCUGGCUGAAGACUGGCCGUGGGGGGUGCAGGGGUCUCCAGCGCUCUGCCCUCCAGCCUGCUUCCUCCCUGCCCACACCGCACUAGGGGAAGGGCCUUUCCUGCUGCCUGCGGGGCCGCACCUGGAGUAGGUAAUGCCAUGUGGUGACGUGAAUGGAGCAGAGGUCUGUGCCCCAUCACACCGCCUUGCUGUUUUUACUGUGGGACAAAAGCACUCUGAUCUGCGUGUUCCGGGGGCCCUCCUACCAGCCGACUUGACGGGAAGUCAGGGUUCAGGUAUCAUCUGUGCACCUGGGGCGGGGUAGUCUGCACUGAACCUGCCAGAGUCCCCUCCUCAUUUCACUGAAAGUCACAGUCUCCAGGGCUGUGUUGCUAACCUUACGUUCUCUCCGUUUGCUUAAUCUAUUAAGAGCCCUAACAGGAGAGGAUGGGCUUUCUCUGUUGUCUGGGGCCCUGCUGUUGGCCGGUGCUCUUAGCAAGAGGUCAUUUUUCUAGGUUGCGCUGGGACAUUGUGAGUUUGGUGAGGGUCAUGGAUGUGGGCUGGGCUGGGCUGGGCUGGGCCGGGCUGCCUGCUGCCUGCUGCUCCCCUACCUGAAAUGCAGCUAGUGCGGCUCUGCCCUUCCUGGGGCUGAGGAAGGCUUCUGCAGGAUAGCUGGGGGGCUGGGCAGGUGGGUGAGGCAGCCUCCCUGCUGACACUCAGUCCUUGUAGCUGGAGCAAGAUCUCCUGAUCCAGGUACGGGCCUGUCUGCUCCAAGAAAGACUCUGCCACCAGAUGCAAAGGGGCCCUUUGUUUUAACUUAGUCCCUGGGGACCGCCUGAUUCAGCACCUGUCGGCCCAGGAUACCCCGCUGGUGGGGACAAGUGCCUGAGUGUGGGCCGUGCCCGAGUGUGGCCAUCCCUGAGUGGGGCCGUCCUGACUAGGAAGUGGCUUUUCAGUUGUGAUGUGUGGGCCUGACCUAGGGGGCGCUGUGGAACCCGGGCUGGAACCAGCCCUCUGUGCCAGGCCGCAGACAGGUUCCGCCGGCCCUGAGGGGCAGCUGCCAUGGCGUGGGUCACUGGGAGCUGAGAGGAAGGGCCCCCACCGCACCUCAGGCAAAGCGGCUCUGGGAACACCUUGAUUUCGUCCAUGUGAGCCGUCCCAGGGAGGGCAGCCAAGCUGUGAAGCCUGAGAAACUGACCUGUGUGCCACGAGCUUGUGGUCUGCUGCCCGGUGGAGGAAGUGCAGGUGCGCCCAGGCUCCUCAUUCCGUUUUGCAGGAUUCCUUCGGGGUGUGAGCAUUUCCUAUUCAGCCUGUCGCCCCCGGGGAGCACGGGCUGGCUCUGUGGUGCCCGUGGCCUUUUGUAGAAGCGUUGGUUUUACGGCAGGUUCAUCUCUGGGGCAGCCUCCCACAGUGGGUGGGGCUUUGCCAGCAGUGCCCACGGGGGUCAUGGGGCCAGGCGCGCUCCGGCGCCUGCAGAACUGAUCGGGGAUAGUCUCAGGAGGCGCUAGUCACGUGCCCCGGUGAUCGGGGAUAGUCUCAGAAGGCGCUAGUCUCCUGCCCCGGUGAUCGGGGAUAGUCUCAGGAGGCACGAGUCGCCUGCCUCGGUGAUGCACCGUUUCUCACACCGGCUGCUCUGGCCCGAGCUAAAGGGGAAGACGUGUGCGGAUAGGAGCUGCACACAAUUUUCCUCCAUGUAUUGUUUAUUUUGCUUUUUCUUUUGGCUAGACAUUAGGAAUUUCAGUUUUCCCAAGUUGUAUUUUUCCUUUUCUAUUUUAAAAUUAUCAUGCAGGGCUGGGUGAGGUCGCUCACGCCUAUAGUCUCAAAACUUUGGGAGGCUGAGGGGGGAGGAUGGCAUGAGCCCAGGAGUUUAAGGCUGCAGUGAGCCGAGAUCGCUCCACUGUCCUCCAGCCUGCAUGACAGAGCGAGACCCUAUCUCAGGAAAAAAAAAAACAAAACUAUUAUGCAGUAGUUUCGACCCUGGAAGACGAGUGUGCAUCUUUGAGUUGUAACACGUGUACCUCGCCCAUCCAGGCGUAGUUUCAUUUGGAAUCUGGUUAUCCUGUAGUUGCUUUGUUAAAAAUAUAUGUAAUUGCAAAUCAUUU